GUUUUAUUUGAAGACAUCGUCCAGUUCUGACCAUGGACUCGCAGCCAUCGGCCCUUAGUUUCCAUCCCCUCUAGUGGGCCUUCGGGGGCUCUACUGACGUCCCUCCUUCCCUUGGUACCGGGCCGGGGAAGUGUUCUCGGGCGCGGGAGGUUCCGCAUGCCCAGGCCUGGCCAGGGGAGAUGACCGAUCCGUCGCUGGGGCUGACAGUCCCCAUGGCGCCGCCUCUGGCCCCGCUCCCUCCCCGGGACCCAAACGGGGCGGGAUCCGAGUGGAGAAAGCCCGGGGCCGUGAGCUUCGCCGACGUGGCCGUGUACUUCUCCCGGGAGGAGUGGGGCUGCCUGCGGCCCGCGCAGAGGGCCCUGUACCGGGACGUGAUGCGGGAGACCUACGGCCACCUGGGCGCGCUCGGUGAGAGCCCCACCUGCUUGCCUGGGCCCUGCGCCUCCACAGGCCCUGCCGCGCCUCUGGGAGCUGCGUGUGGAGUUGGGGGCCCCGGGGCCGGGCAGGCGGCCUCCUCGCAGCGUGGGGUUUGCGUUCUUCUCCCCCAGGAGUCGGAGGCAGCAAGCCGGCGCUCAUCUCCUGGGUGGAGGAGAAGGCCGAACUGUGGGAUCCGGCUGCCCAGGAUCCGGAGGUGGCGAAGUGUCCGACAGAAGCGGACCCAGCAGAUUCCAGAAACAAGGAAGAGGAAAGACAAAGGGAAGGGACGGGAGCCCUGGAGAAGCCCGACCCUGUGGCCGCCGGGUCUCCUGGGCUGAAGGCUCCCCAAGCCCCCUUUGCCGGGUUGGAGCAGCUGUCCAAGGCCCGGCGCCGGAGUCGCCCCCGCUUUUUUGCCCACCCCCCUGUCCCCCGAGCUGACCAGCGUCACGGCUGCUACGUGUGCGGGAAGAGCUUCGCCUGGCGCUCCACACUGGUGGAGCACAUUUACAGCCACAGGGGCGAGAAGCCCUUCCACUGCGCAGACUGCGGCAAGGGCUUCGGCCACGCUUCCUCCCUGAGCAAACACCGGGCCAUCCAUCGUGGGGAGCGGCCCCACCGCUGUCCCGAGUGUGGUCGGGCCUUCAUGCGCCGCACGGCGCUGACUUCUCACCUGCGCGUUCACACUGGCGAGAAGCCCUACCGCUGCCCGCAGUGUGGCCGCUGCUUCGGCCUGAAGACCGGCAUGGCCAAGCACCAAUGGGUCCAUCGGCCCGGGGGCGAGGGGCGUAGGGGCCGGCGCCCUGGGGGGCUGUCUGUGACCCUGACUCCUGUCCGCGGGGACCUGGACCCGCCUGUGGGCUUCCAGCUGUAUCCAGAGAUAUUCCAGGAAUGUGGGUGACGGCCUAAAAAGUGACCAUCUAGACAUUGUGGGCGGCCCGAGAUGGGCUCAGGGGCCCGAACCUCUGCAGCGGCCUGCAGGGAGGUCCCAGAAUCCACCGCAAGAGCUGGCCUGGGGUGCGGACAGUCUGAUCUUGGGCUCUCAGCAGCCUCUUCUGCCAGCACCUUGCUCCCCGCUGCCCUGGGCUCUCCAAGGCCCCCUUUGCUGAGGCAGGGCUGAGGUGAGAACCCCCCAGACCUCCAUACAGGGAAGCAAAAGCUGUUUCUCCUCCCAGAGAUGCUAAGAGGAUUGAGGUAGAGAAGAACCUUGUUUUCUCUGUUGUCUUUUUCUUUUUACUUUUUUAAUUUUUUGAGACGGAGUUUUGCUCUUGUUGCCCAGGCUGGAGUGCAAUGGUGCGAUCUCGACUCACUGCAACUUCCACCUCCUGGAGUCAAGCGAUUCUCCUGCCUCAGCCACCCAAGUAGCUGGAAUUACAGGCACCUGCCACUAUGCCCGGCUAACUUUUUGUAUUUUUAGUAGAGAUGGGGUUUCACCAUGUUGGCUAGGCUGGUCUCGAACUCCUGCCCUCAGGUGAUCCACCCACCUCUGCCUCCCAAAGUGCUGGGAUUACAGGCGUGAGCCACCUCACCUGGCCUUUUCUUUUUUAUUCUUUGACCUUCCCACAAGACAAUACCCAUUGUCUGUUUUUUUUGUUUAUUUAUUUACUUAUUAAGACAGCAUCUUGCUCCUCACCCAGGCUGGAAUGCAGUGGUGUGAACUGGGCUCACUGCAGCCUAGACCUGCUGGGCUCAAGGAAUCCUCCUGCCCCAGCCUCUCAGAUGGCUGUGACUACAGGUGGGCAACACUAUGCCUGGCUAAUUUUUAAAUUUUUUUGCAGAGAUGGGGUUCCCACUAUGUUGAUCAGGCUGGUCUCAAACUCCUCGGUUCAAGCAAUUCGCCCACCUUGGCCUCCCAAAGUGCUGGGAUUACAGGGGAGCCACUGCACUGGCCUUCAUUGUCUUUUUGCUGCACAACCUAAAAAACCAGUGACCCUGUAUUGGAUCUCGCCUGCAGUUGCUGUAUUGAUUUGGGCCCAGGCAGUGUUUUUAAGUGAUAAGAAUUAGUGAUGAAGAUCUAAAGGGAUAUUUUGCACCAAAAUCCAGGUUUCUGGCAUCUCUUGAAAAAUCCAAAGAUUUCGCAAGUUCACCUAGGCUCUCAGAAAGUCGCAGUUGUUGGGAGUUGGGCCGGAGCCAGAACUCCCAACUUACUGUGGUCCGGCCACUCAUCCCAUCAGCUCCUGACCAAGCAUGAGUAGCCAUUCAUCAUGGCUUGCUUUUAGUGUUUUUGGUGUUUAUCUUAAAGUACAGCAAAGAAGAAAGGGAAGUAUUUCUUGAACCCAUGUCUGUGUCAAAACAGUCCUUGCAUCUUUCCUGUCUUUAGGUACGCACCAUCUUUGCUGUCUUUAAGUAUGUGCCAUCAUGGGCAGAGGGGGCUAGGCCAGGAACACCUGGUGUUAGAUUUGUAGCCAGUGGCAACCGUACCCAUCUGUAUCCCCAAGUUCUACACGGAAUCCCUCCAGCACUUCACGACUCCAUUAUCCAGCUACCACUAAUUCCUUUGUGGGCAGAGUCCAGCCACGGGCAGCCCCUGCCCUGCCUCUGGUCAGGACAACACCUGCCCAAGGAGAGCAAGGGCCUGUGACCUCUGCUGGCCUGUGCGCCCUCACCUGUCACCCAGCUCAGCCCUGUGUCUGGCCUACCCAGGGAGGAAGGAACCAGAUUUAUCAGCCUGAAAGGAGGUAGAAGUUUUGGAGAAAAGACACUGUUCGGGUGUCAAGUAAUGAACUGACUUUAUUCGAACCUCAUCUCCAAUCCAAUCCCACCGUGGUCUCUCUCUCCCUCAGCUUUUCUGGGGCGGGUUGACUCGUGUGUCACUUUAUCACAGGGGCACAUGGGGUGAGAAGAGGAACCUUGGCAGUAGGAGAUACCUUUGUACCAGGUUUUAAUUUCCAGUGUACAUCUCAGUCCCCUCCCCUAACCCUCAACACAGCCUGGGGAAAGCCCAGCUUGCAACACCAGUUCUCAGCCCAGACUGACAGCCAGAUAGAUCUUGGCCCUGAGUUUGCCAAUUAAAGAUGCCGUGAUUAUUACCUA